AGACUUCCUGUGUGUCUGACCACGGACAACACACAGCUCUGCCAUCCACGAGCUGCAUUGUAAGUGAAGCUGGGUUAAAGGUAUGUAGAAUAAUGAUUGCUAUUAUUUGUUUAAAUAUUAUUUCUUAGAAGAAGGGGACAGAGUGCAGUUUGUAAACACUGGUUUAAAAACUCCUUUCUUUUAGAAAGGAGAGAAAGUGAAAUGUAAAAAACACAUAUUUGUGCUGAACCAUGAAUGAUACCGUCACUGAAAUAUCUAAAAACCAUAUUGCUUAAAGGCACUUCUUGCAAUGUGUAAUUCAGCUAAGAUGAUAAUCAAAUGCAUAGCUCUUGAAUACAGAAAAAUGAUACAGAUCCUCCUCCUUUGCUGCCCUUCCCACAGAAUACUGAGAUAAAACUUACUGAGGCCUAGCUACCAAAGGCAGAAUUAGUUGUUCCAUAUCCUAGGCUAGCAUUUGGUACAUAGUCCCUAUUUUAUCAUGAUUACUGAGAACUGUUAAGUCUAACUCAACUGUGUAGAUCAAGACAGUUUUGUCUUAGUGCAUCCAGCGGCUGAAGCACAGUUGGCACGCUGUAGAUUUUGUGUUGUUGCGGUGAGACCACCAGUUAGAAUAAAGAGCUGAUUUGGGCCGGGUUUGGUGGCUCACACCUGUAAUCCUGGUGCUUUGGGAGACCAAGGCCAGAGGAUUGCUUGAGGCCAGGAGUUCAAGACCCACCUGGGCAACACAGUAGAACCACGUCCCUAAAAAAUUUUAAAAAUAAAUUGGCCAGGUGGAGUGGCCUGUGCCUUUAGUUCCAGUUACUUGGGAGGCUGAGAUGGGAGGAUCUCUUGAGGCCAGGAGUUCGAGGUUACAGUGAGUCAUGAUUGUGCCACUGCACUCCAGCCUGGGCUACGUAAGGCAAGACUGGCUCUAAAAAAAAUUUGCUUUUUAAUGAAAAAAAAAAAAAGAGCUGAUUUGGCUCUUUCUUCCCCCAUUUACCCAGAAUUGCUAAAGUGGUAGAUACUGACAAGGUAUCUUAGCAGGGCAGAAGUCUCAUGGUUUGAGUCAGUUGGGACCAAUUGCUGUUGAUGUGAAUUUCUAACUCCUUUGUCAUUCUGAGUGUGUCAGCUGAAUUCACAUAAGGGCAUUCACCAAGGGAGGAAGAGAAAGGCCUUUAGUUUUAAUUAUUUUAUAGUUGAGAAAAUUAGACACAUACUCGGGGUUACGGGGUCUAUUCUGAUUUUUAUUACUCCUAGAAAUUUCAUACAGAUUAUAAUCUGUCUAUCUUGUUAGUAAUAUCUGACUGAAUUUUUUGGAAUAGCUAUGUGUAGAACCCAUUUUAUUACACAGAUUUAGGAAUCUCAGAGGAUCUGAUUCCUUAGUCUCUUAAAUCUUCAGUGGCAUUAAAUGCCAACACAUUGUCCUUGGUCAAGACUACAACGUAGAAAGGAACAAGCUAAUUAACUACUUAGAAUUCCCUCUCCUAAGAGACCACAUCGCCAAAGUGGCACCAUGACACAGCUUGGUGUUUUGUUGGUCACUUUAGGAGAACACCAUUUUGGAGGCCUUGGGUGGAGCUGGAGAUAGAGCCAUGGAGGUAGAAUCGUGUCGGAAAACCUGGGUUUAGCCCCAUUUUGUACUUGGGCGUUUGAGCUAAUCGCUUAAGUCACGUAAAACAACAAGACUAAUAAAGUCUGGGAUACAGACUUUAACACCUCAAGUGCUGCCAAAAGUAUUUAGAAGACAAAGCGAAUCAUAGGCACCCUUCACCGAGCACCUCCUAGACAUCAAGAACCAUGCUAGGUUCCCUACAUUCUUCAUUUAAUGCCAAUAACCCCACGAGGCAGUUAUCACCUUCAUUCUACAAAUGGGCCCCACUCCUACCAAUUAACUGGCUGAAUCAGGAUCUGACCCCGGGCCUGCCAACGCUCCCGCUGGUGGAUUGCCCGCCUUGUCAGCUCGAGUUGGCAGGACGUGGGAGUAAAAACCCGGCGCCCCAGCCUUCACCGUGCUGCACGAGGAAGCUGGCUAGGCAGGCAUGACUUUGUCAGUCAACCAUCCCGCAGCCGGGCCCUGGGCUUUGUUAGCAGCCACUUGGCGAGGGCCCCGGGCGGGUGGGGAGGCGGCGCUUCCUCCAAGAGGAGGUGGGACCCCGGCCCCGACGACCUCGGAGCCGCCCCCGGCCCCGGAUCGCCGACGACACCUCUCGCUGCUUCAGGAGGACCUGCAGGAGGACGCAGACGGAUUUGGUGUGGAUGACUACAGCUCAGAGUCUGAUGUGAUUAUUAUACCUUCAGCCCUGGACUUUGUCUCACAAGAUGAAAUGUUGACGCCCCUGGGGAGAUUGGACAAGUAUGCUGCAAGUGAGAACAUAUUUAACAGACAAAUGGUGGCCCGGAGUUUGCUCGAUACCUUGAGGGAAGUCUGCGAUGAUGAAAGAGAUUGUAUUGCUGUUUUGGAAAGAAUUAGCAGAUUGGCCGAUGAUUCAGAACCAACUGUGAGAGCGGAGCUGAUGGAACAGGUGCCUCACAUCGCACUGUUUUGUCAAGAAAACCGGCCUUCAAUACCAUAUGCUUUUUCAAAAUUCUUACUACCUAUUGUGGUUAGAUACCUUGCAGAUCAGAAUAAUCAGGUGAGGAAAACAAGUCAGGCAGCUUUGCUGGCUCUGUUGGAGCAGGAGCUCAUUGAACGAUUUGAUGUGGAGACCAAAGUGUGCCCUGUCCUCAUAGAGCUGACAGCCCCAGAUAGCAAUGAUGAUGUGAAAACAGAAGCUGUGGCUAUAAUGUGCAAAAUGGCUCCCAUGGUUGGGAAGGAUAUUACAGAGCGUCUUAUCCUCCCUAGGUUUUGUGAGAUGUGCUGCGAUUGCAGAAUGUUUCACGUUCGAAAGGUCUGUGCUGCCAAUUUUGGAGAUAUUUGCAGUGUAGUUGGCCAGCAAGCUACUGAAGAAAUGUUGCUGCCCAGAUUUUUCCAGCUUUGUUCUGAUAAUGUAUGGGGAGUCCGAAAGGCUUGUGCUGAAUGCUUCAUGGCGGUUUCAUGUGCAACAUGUCAAGAAAUCCGACGGACCAAAUUAUCAGCACUUUUUAUUAAUUUGAUCAGUGAUCCUUCACGUUGGGUUCGCCAAGCAGCUUUUCAGUCUCUGGGACCUUUCAUAUCUACUUUUGCUAAUCCAUCUAGCUCAGGCCAGUAUUUUAAAGAAGAAAGCAAAAGUUCAGAAGAGAUGUCAGUAGAAAACAAAAAUAGGACCAGAGAUCAAGAAGCCCCAGAGGAUGUACAAGUCAGGCCAGAGGAUACUCCUUCAGAUCUCAGUGUUAGUAAUUCCAGUGUCAUACUGGAAAACACGAUGGAAGACCAUGCUGCUGAGGCAUCCGGGAAGCCUCUAGGUGAAAUUAGUGUUCCACUGGACAGCUCUUUACUUUGUACUUUGUCCUCAGAAUCUCACCAGGAAGCAGCUAGUAAUGAGAAUGAUAAAAAACCUGGUAACUACAAAUCUAUGUUACGACCAGAGGUUGGCACCACUUCACAAGAUUCAGCUCUCUUAGAUCAGGAAUUGUAUAACUCCUUCCAUUUCUGGAGGACUCCUCUUCCUGAAAUAGAUCUAGACAUAGAGCUUGAACAGAACUCUGGGGGAAAACCCAGCCCAGAGGGACCAGAGGAAGAAUCUGAGGGCCCUGUGCCCAGUUCUCCAAACAUCACCAUGGCCACCAGAAAGGAACUGGAAGAAAUGAUAGAAAAUCUAGAGCCCCACAUUGAUGAUCCAGAUGUUAAAGCACAAGUGGAAGUGCUGUCCGCUGCACUACGUGCUUCCAGCCUGGAUGCACAUGAAGAGACCAUCAGUAUAGAAAAGAGAAGUGAUUUGCAAGAUGAACUGGAUAUAAAUGAGCUACCAAAUUGUAAAAUAAAUCAAGAAGAUUCUGUGCCUUUAAUCAGCGAUGCUGUUGAGAAUAUGGACUCCACUCUUCACUAUAUUCACAGCGAUUCAGACUUGAGCAACAAUAGCAGUUUUAGCCCUGAUGAGGAAAGGAGAACUAAAGUACAAGAUGUUGUACCUCAGGCGUUGUUAGAUCAGUAUUUAUCUAUGACUGACCCUUCUCGUGCACAGACGGUUGACACUGAAAUUGCUAAGCACUGUGCAUAUAGCCUCCCUGGUGUGGCCUUGACACUCGGAAGACAGAAUUGGCACUGCCUGAGAGAGACGUAUGAGACUCUGGCCUCAGACAUGCAGUGGAAAGUUCGACGAACUCUAGCAUUCUCCAUCCACGAGCUUGCAGUUAUUCUUGGAGAUCAAUUGACAGCUGCAGAUCUGGUUCCAAUUUUUAAUGGAUUUUUAAAAGACCUCGAUGAAGUCAGGAUAGGUGUUCUUAAACACUUGCAUGAUUUUCUGAAGCUUCUUCAUAUUGACAAAAGAAGAGAAUAUCUUUAUCAACUUCAGGAGUUUUUGGUGACAGAUAAUAGUAGAAAUUGGCGGUUUCGAGCUGAACUGGCUGAACAGCUGAUUUUACUUCUAGAGUUAUAUAGUCCCAGAGAUGUUUAUGACUAUUUACGUCCCAUUGCUCUGAAUCUGUGUGCAGACAAAGUUUCUUCUGUUCGUUGGAUUUCCUACAAGUUGGUCAGCGAGAUGGUGAAGAAGCUGCACGCGGCAACACCACCAACGUUCGGAGUGGACCUCAUCAAUGAGCUUGUGGAGAACUUUGGCAGAUGUCCCAAGUGGUCUGGUCGGCAAGCCUUUGUCUUUGUCUGCCAGACUGUCAUUGAGGAUGACUGCCUUCCCAUGGACCAGUUUGCUGUGCAUCUCAUGCCGCAUCUGCUAACCUUAGCAAAUGACAGGGUUCCUAACGUGCGAGUGCUGCUUGCAAAGACAUUAAGACAAACUCUACUAGAAAAAGACUAUUUCUUGGCCUCUGCCAGCUGCCACCAGGAGGCUGUGGAGCAGACCAUCAUGGCUCUUCAGAUGGACCGUGACAGCGAUGUCAAGUAUUUUGCAAGCAUCCACCCUGCCAGUACCAAAAUCUCCGAAGAUGCCAUGAGCACAGCGUCCUCAACCUACUAGAAGGCUUGAAUCUCGGUGUCUUUCCUGCUUCCAUGAGAGCCGAGGUUCAGUGGGCAUUCGCCACGCAUGUGACCUGGGAUAGCUUUCGGGGGAGGAGAGACCUUCCUCUCCUGCGGACUUCAUUGCAGGUGCAAGUUGCCUACACCCAAUACCAGGGAUUUCAAGAGUCAAGAGAAAGUACAGUAAACACUAUUAUCUUAUCUUGACUUUAAGGGGAAAUAAUUUCUCAGAGGAUUAUAAUUGUCACCGAAGCCUUAAAUCCUUCUGUCUUCCUGACUGAAUGAAACUUGAAUUGGCAGAGCAUUUUCCUUAUGGAAGGGAUGAGAUUCCCAGAGACCUGCAUUGCUUUCUCCUGGUUUUAUUUAACAAUCGACAAAUGAAAUUCUUACAGCCUGAAGGCAGACGUGUGCCCAGAUGUGAAAGAGACCUUCAGUAUCAGCCCUAACUCUUCUCUCCCAGGAAGGACUUGCUGGGCUCUGUGGCCAGCUGUCCAGCCCAGCCCUGUGUGUGAAUCGUUUGUGACGUGUGCAAAUGGGAAAGGAGGGGUUUUUACAUCUCCUAAAGGACCUGAUGCCAACACAAGUAGGAUUGACUUAAACUCUUAAGCGCAGCAUAUUGCUGUACACAUUUACAGAAUGGUUGCUGAGUGUCUGUGUCUGAUUUUUUCAUGCUGGUCAUGACCUGAAGGAAAUUUAUUAGACGUAUAAUGUAUGUCUGGUGUUUUUAACUUGAUCAUGAUCAGCUCUGAGGUGCAACUUCUUCACAUACUGUACAUACCUGUGACCACUCUUGGGAGUGCUGCAGUCUUUAAUCAUGCUGUUUAAACUGUUGUGGCACAAGUUCUCUUGUCCAAAUAAAAUUUAUUAAUAAGAUCUAUAGAGAGAGAUAUAUACACUUUUGAUUGUUUUCUAGAUGUCUACCAAUAAAUGCAAUUUGUGACCUGUAUUAAUGAUUUAAAGUGGGGAAACUAGAUUAAAAUAUUUGUCUUUUAACUA